GUCUGAGCCCUCCUUGGCUCUUACAAUGCUCACUUGUUUUCACAAUGCAGCAAAAUGAAAUGCCUUAGAAAAAGAGUAACAUUCCAGAAAACGGUGUAAUUUAUUUUUCUUCCUUAAUUGCCCCAUCUGUGGAGGAUUUCUUUGCUGAACACCACAUCAAAGAGUUCACCCGGAGGACCAGCAGGGUGACGCACAGCUUCUCCAAGAAACUGGCUUGCAGACCUGGGGGGAGGGACACUGAGUACAGUUCUAGGAGUGGCCACCCCACAGUCACUGAGAUCAGGCUUUCCAGGGAUCUUCUGCAUUUAAAAUAGAAGAGGCAUCAUGCUGAAGAGGGAGGGGAAGGUCCAACCUUACACUAAAACCCUGGAUGGAGGAUGGGGAUGGAUGAUUGUGAUUCAUUUUUUCCUGGUGAAUGUGUUUGUGAUGGGGAUGACCAAGACUUUUGCAAUUUUCUUUGUGGUCUUUCAAGAAGAGUUUGAAGGCACCUCAGAGCAAAUUGGUUGGAUUGGAUCCAUCAUGUCAUCUCUUCGUUUUUGUGCAGGUCCCCUGGUUGCUAUUAUUUGUGACAUACUUGGAGAGAAAACUACCUCCAUUCUUGGGGCUUUCGUUGUUACUGGUGGAUAUCUGAUCAGCAGCUGGGCCACAAGUAUUCCUUUUCUUUGUGUGACUAUGGGACUUCUACCCGGUUUGGGUUCUGCUUUCUUAUACCAAGUGGCUGCUGUGGUAACUACCAAAUACUUCAAAAAACGAUUGGCUCUUUCUACAGCUAUUGCCCGUUCUGGGAUGGGACUGACUUUUCUUUUGGCACCCUUUACAAAAUUCCUGAUAGAUCUGUAUGACUGGACAGGAGCCCUUAUAUUAUUUGGAGCUAUCGCAUUGAAUUUGGUGCCUUCUAGUAUGCUCUUAAGACCCAUCCAUAUCAAAAGUGAGAACAAUUCUGGUAUUAAAGAUAAAGGCAGCAGUUUGUCUGCACAUGGUCCAGAGGCACAUGCAACAGAAACACACUGCCAUGAGACAGAAGAGUCUACCAUCAAGGACAGUACUACGCAGAAGGCUGGACUACCUAGCAAAAAUUUAACAGUCUCACAAAAUCAAAGUGAAGAGUUCUACAAUGGGCCUAACAGGAACAGACUGUUAUUAAAGAGUGAUGAAGAAAGUGAUAAGGUUAUUUCGUGGAGCUGCAAACAACUGUUUGACAUUUCUCUCUUUAGAAAUCCUUUCUUCUACAUAUUUACUUGGUCUUUUCUCCUCAGUCAGUUAGCAUACUUCAUCCCUACCUUUCACCUGGUAGCCAGAGCCAAAACACUGGGGAUUGACAUCAUGGAUGCCUCUUACCUUGUUUCUGUAGCAGGUAUCCUUGAGACGGUCAGUCAGAUUAUUUCUGGAUGGGUUGCUGAUCAAAACUGGAUUAAGAAGUAUCAUUACCACAAGUCUUACCUCAUCCUCUGCGGCAUCACUAACCUGCUUGCUCCUUUAGCCACCACAUUUCCACUACUUAUGACCUACACCAUCUGCUUUGCCAUCUUUGCUGGUGGUUACCUGGCAUUGAUACUGCCUGUACUGGUUGAUCUGUGUAGGAAUUCUACAGUAAACAGGUUUUUGGGACUUGCCAGUUUCUUUGCUGGGAUGGCUGUCCUUUCUGGACCACCUAUAGCAGGCUGGUUAUAUGAUUAUACCCAGACAUACAAUGGCUCUUUCUACUUCUCUGGCAUAUGCUAUCUCCUCUCUUCAGUUUCCUUUUUUUUUGUACCAUUGGCCGAAAGAUGGAAAAACAGUCUGACCUGAAAGAAAGAAGACUGCAAUCAAGUGAGAGCUAAACAAAAGAAAACCUAAACUAAUGUCAUUGGAAACAAAAGCUUGAAAGAAACACAUCGCAUCUACAUUUGUAACAUGAGAAGGAAAACAAUUUUUUUUUUUUUUUUUUUGAGACGGAGUCUCGCUCUUUCGCCCAGGCUGGAGUGCAGUGGCGCAAUCUCGGCUCACUGUAAUCUCCGCCUCCUGGGUUCAAGGGAUUCUCCUGCCUCAGCCUCCCAAGUAGCUGGGACUACAGGCACACGCCACCACACCCAGCUAAUUUUUUGUAUUUUUAGUAGAGGCGGGGUUUCACCAUGUUAGCCAGGAUGGUCUCCAUCUCCUGACCUCGUGAUCCGCCCGCCUUGUCCUCCAAAGUGCUGGGAUUACAGGCAUGAGCCACUGGGCGCGGCCAGAUAAGUUUUUAAGGUUCCUUCUUGCUUUAGCAUUCUGAGAAAUGUCUAAUUGGUAGUAAGACAAGAGUAAUAGCAACCUGUAUUGUUAGUAUUUAACCAAAUAGGCUAAAAUUUUAAUCAGGUACCUUAUGUAUUAAAUAGAAAUCGGAAUGUACCAUAAUAAAUCCAAACUCUCAAUUACGCCAUGGUAAUUCAGUCACUAAAAUAUGUAAAGAUAGAAAAUUUUUUAAUUUAAAGAAGUGUGAAACAUAGCCAUUGAUUGAUCAGAAUUCUGGAAUCUGAAUAUUAAAACCUUACUUAGUGACUGGAAUGGUAUAUGCUCCCUCCAAAAGUUUAUCUUUGUUUAUUGAUUAAAGGUAAUCCUUACUUUCUUUGUAUUACUUAGGUUCUUAAUUAAAGGUAAUCCUUACUUUCUUUGUAUUACUUAGGUUCUUAAAUUUCUAUGAUAAACAUGUAUUGCUAAAUAAUAAAAAGUAUAUAAAAAUUG